GAGAAAGCGGAAGAUGGCGGCGGCGGCCGGGAGGCCGUGAGGAGAGCGGCGGCUGCGAGGGCGGCCGAUGGCGGCCGGGAGGCGCCCUCGGACACUUGCGGGUCGUUAGGGCGCGACGCUGGGAGGCAUGUCGGAGCACGUGGAGCCCGCAGCUCCGGGGCCCGGGCCCAACGGCGGCGGCGGCGGCCCGGCCCCCGCGCGCGGGCCUCGCACCCCCAAUCUCAACCCCAACCCCCUCAUCAACGUGCGCGACCGGCUCUUCCACGCGCUGUUCUUCAAGAUGGCUGUCACCUAUUCGCGGCUCUUCCCGCCCGCCUUCCGCCGUCUCUUCGAGUUCUUCGUGCUGCUCAAGGCCCUGUUUGUGCUCUUCGUCCUGGCCUACAUCCACAUCGUCUUCUCCCGCUCGCCCAUCAACUGCCUGGAGCAUGUGCGUGACAAGUGGCCGCGUGAGGGCAUCCUGCGUGUGGAAGUGCGGCACAACUCGAGCCGCGCGCCCGUCUUCCUACAGUUCUGUGACAGCGGCGGCCGCGGGAGCUUCCCGGGCCUGGCCGUGGAACCAGGCAGCAACCUGGACAUGGAAGAUGAGGAGGAGGAAGAGCUGACCAUGGAGAUGUUUGGGAACAGCUCCAUCAAGGUCCCUGGUCGCCCACAGUUUGAGCUGGACAUCGAGCCCAAGGUGUUCAAGCCGCCGAGUAGCACAGAGGCCCUGAAUGACAGCCAGGAGUUCCCCUUCCCCGAGACGCCCACCAAAGUGUGGCCGCAGGACGAGUACAUCGUGGAGUACUCACUAGAGUAUGGCUUCCUUCGCCUGUCGCAGGCCACCCGCCAGCGCCUGAGCAUCCCCGUCAUGGUGGUCACCCUGGACCCCACGCGGGACCAGUGCUUCGGGGACCGCUUCAGCCGCCUGCUGCUGGAUGAGUUCCUGGGCUACGAUGACAUCCUCAUGUCCAGCGUGAAGGGCCUGGCCGAGAACGAGGAGAACAAGGGCUUCCUGCGGAAUGUGGUGUCGGGCGAGCACUACCGCUUUGUGAGCAUGUGGAUGGCGCGGACGUCCUACCUGGCCGCCUUCGCCAUCAUGGUCAUCUUCACGCUGAGCGUGUCCAUGCUGCUGCGGUACUCACACCACCAGAUCUUCGUCUUCAUCGUGGACCUGCUGCAGAUGCUGGAGAUGAACAUGGCCAUCGCCUUCCCCGCAGCGCCCCUGCUGACCGUCAUCCUGGCCCUCGUCGGGAUGGAGGCCAUCAUGUCGGAGUUCUUCAACGACACCACCACCGCCUUCUACAUCAUCCUCAUCGUGUGGCUCGCGGACCAGUAUGACGCCAUCUGCUGCCACACCAGCACCAGCAAGCGGCAUUGGCUGCGGUUCUUCUAUCUCUACCACUUCGCCUUCUAUGCCUAUCACUACCGCUUCAAUGGGCAGUAUAGCAGCCUGGCCCUGGUCACCUCCUGGCUCUUCAUCCAGGUGAGGCCUGGGCGGCAAGCAGGGGGCAGGCCAGCCGUGCCUUUCCAGGCAGGAGAGGCUGCAGCCGGGGAGGAUGCCCUGUGGGGUCGGCCCAAGCGGGCAGAGCAUUCCAUGAUCUACUUCUUCCACCACUACGAGCUGCCUGCCAUCCUGCAGCAGGUCCGCAUCCAGGAGAUGCUGCUUCAGGCGCCGCCACUGGGCCCCGGGACCCCCACGGCGCUGCCCGAUGACAUGAACAACAACUCGGGCGCCCCGGCUACAGCCCCUGACUCUGCCGGCCAGCCCCCCGCCCUGGGCCCCGUCUCGCCUGGGGCCAGCGGGAGUCCCGGGCCUGUGGCAGCGGCGCCCAGCUCCCUGGUGGCCGCGGCAGCCUCAGUGGCAGCAGCUGCCGGUGGUGACCUGGGUUGGAUGGCAGAGACCGCUGCCAUCAUCACAGACGCCUCCUUCCUGUCCGGCCUGAGCGCCUCCCUCCUGGAGCGGCGUCCAGCCAGCCCGCUGGGCCCUGCUGGGGGCCUCCCCCACGCCCCCCAGGACAGUGUCCCCCCGAGUGACUCCGCAGCUUCUGACACAACUCCCCUGGGGGCUGCGGUAGGCGGGCCUAGCCCGGCCUCCAUGGCCCCAACGGAGGCGCCCUCGGAGGUGGGGUCCUGAGCCGCACAGCUGAGCCGCCUCUGACCCCUGCUGGCUGGGCCUGACCUUCCCGAGCCCGUGGGGGUGGGGGAGGCCAGCCACCUCCUUCCUCUGGGACUGCCCAGCCUGUGUCGGGGGCUUUCAGGGUUUCGUGGGGUUUGCCCGGAAGGCGGCUUUCCUCCCCCUGGUGUGAGGUCGCGCCCGAGGCUUGUACCCGCUAGUGAGGUGUUUGAGCUGGUCAGCAAGGAGAGGGGGUGGGGUUCCGCGGAAGGUUCUGGAGGGGUCUUGGUAGGUCUGCAGUGAACCGUCCUGAGGAUGGAGUGGGGUCCCAUGGUGCAGGUCUCUGAGCAAGGCGGAGGUGUGGAGGAGAGGCCGGCUUGGGGUGGGGCCUCGCGCCCUAGUGCCGGCCGGCCUCAGCCCGGCUCUGCCUGGUGCUCCCUGCAGUGCCUUCUCCAUGGCCCCGCCCUCCCCGCGUGUGCGCCAGGCUUGGGGUCCCCGGGAGAGCAGAGCUUGCGCCUCGGGCAUAGGGACGUGGGGUGCAGGCGCCAACAUCAGUGGCAGCAGCCAGGGCCGUGGUCCAGUCCCACUCGGGGAUGGAGUGGGCCGGCGGCCAAACCAGUCACUCGGGGAGGAAUGCGGAGGAGCGCUCAUUCCAUUCUAUUUAAUUGCAGUGUACAAAAUUGUGUUUGUAUAUAGAAUAAACUGUCUGUUGACAGCG